GUGAACAGCGCAGUGAUAAAGCCUGGCGUUCUCCACCUGCAGGCGGAGGCUGACGGCGCGGUCUUUGGCGCGAGUCCGUGCACCGCGGCCGCCCCGCCCCGGUGGGAGAGAGGGACGGAGGAAGCUGCAGGUAUAACGGGAGGAGAGCGCCAGGCGGAGCUGGGGCGUCCCUCCCGCUCGCUUCUUGACUCGCGUUGCUGCCGGCCGCCUCCCGCGCCUAGUGUCCGGGACGCGCCUGAACCUGCCGCCUCCGUGCCUGGGGUGGCGCCGCGCGGCCCCGAGCGCUCCAGAAAGCUGCGGCGCGAGUCCGCGGGGCCGACCUCGGAGACGCAGCUGGGGCCGGGCGCGGCUUGGCGGGAGGGUCUGCAGCGCCGAGGGAGGCUGCUAGUGCGUGAGGAAGAGAGCUAGAGACUGGACACGGGAGACAGAGCAGCGUCAGAGCCGCGCAGGGGACGGGAGUGAGAGCAGGAGCGACGCAGAGCGGCCGUCGCCGUGCCCGGGUCUCAGGGCGCCUGGCUGAAGUGAGCAUGGCUUCAGUGGCCUGGGCCGUCCUCAAGGUGCUGCUGCUUCUCCCCACUCAGACUUGGAGCCCCGUGGGAGCAGGAAAUCCACCUGACUGUGAUGCCCCACUGGCCUCUGCCUUGCCUAGGUCAUCCUUCAGCAGCUCCUCAGAGCUGUCCAGCAGCCACGGCCCGGGGUUUUCAAGGCUUAAUCGAAGAGAUGGAGCUGGUGGCUGGACUCCACUUGUGUCAAAUAAAUACCAAUGGCUGCAAAUUGACCUUGGAGAGAGAAUGGAGGUCACUGCUGUCGCCACCCAAGGAGGAUAUGGGAGCUCUGACUGGGUGACCAGCUACCUCCUGAUGUUCAGUGAUGGUGGGAGAAACUGGAAGCAGUAUCGCCGAGAAGAAAGCAUCUGGGGUUUUCCAGGAAACACAAACGCAGACAGUGUGGUGCACUACAGACUCCAGCCUCCCUUUGAAGCCAGGUUCCUGCGCUUUCUCCCUUUAGCCUGGAACCCUAGGGGCAGGAUUGGGAUGCGGAUCGAAGUGUACGGAUGUGCAUAUAAAUCUGAGGUGGUUUAUUUUGAUGGACAAAGUGCUCUGCUGUAUAGACUUGAUAAAAAACCUUUAAAACCAAUAAGAGACGUUAUUUCUUUGAAAUUUAAAGCCAUGCAGAGCAAUGGAAUUCUACUUCACAGAGAAGGACAACAUGGAAAUCACAUUACUCUGGAAUUAAUUAAAGGAAAGCUUGUCUUUUUUCUUAAUUCAGGCAAUGCUAAGCUGCCUUCCACUAUUGCUCCUGUGACCCUCACCCUGGGCAGCCUGCUGGACGACCAGCACUGGCAUUCCGUCCUCAUCGAGCUCCUCGACACGCAGGUCAACUUCACCGUGGACAAACACACUCAUCAUUUCCAAGCAAAGGGAGAUUCCAGUUACUUGGAUCUUAAUUUUGAGAUCAGCUUUGGGGGAAUUCCGACACCCGGAAGAUCGCGGGCAUUCAGACGUAAAAGCUUUCAUGGGUGUUUAGAAAAUCUUUAUUAUAAUGGAGUGGAUGUUACCGAAUUAGCCAAGAAACACAAACCACAGAUCCUCAUGAUGGAGUUGGCUCAUGGGUUGCAGGACCAAAACCUGAAAAUAUCUCUGACUGUGUGUCACCAGACCACACAAUGAAUACAUCACUUAGGUUAGCAUGAGAAAAAGGGAAAAACAGCUGUGAAGCCCAUGAACUUUCCAAGAAGGUAAAGGAGAAAAAAAAAAAAAAAAAAGAUGGGUUUGAAGUCUAAGUUUUACUAUGAACAGCACCCUGCUGAGAUCAUAAAAAUGAAAAAUACCAUCAAGAUACAUGAAAAAGGAAACACCAAAGGGAAGAGUGAUAACAAGGCUCCACAGAGUGCAGUUUCCUUUGACAAGAUGAAAAAGAAAUGAAAAGAGGAAGGAGAUAAAUGGAACAGCCCUCUACCUAAAGUUUCUGUCCAUGGAGAAACUGACAUUUAAGUGCUGCUCAACAGGAAAAAGAAAAAAGACCUGGUUAUUGAAGUUGGCUUUGUUGGAGAUGCGUUACUCAGAUACAGAUACAAAGAUGGGUUUGGCCAAUGGGCAUCCGUGUCAAGAAGCCUGACCUAACACGUUCUGAAUAUUAAGCUACCUUUUAUCUGCCAGUCCUUGGUGUUCAGAAGAAUCCCUCCUCCUCACCCUAACUUCUAUGGGGCUAUUUACAAAGACACUGUCAUUGAAGUGAGGAAGAGUGAGUUGGGCCUUAUGACACAAAGAGACAAGACUAUUUGAGGACAACAGACACAGGUUUUCAUAUACAUUCCAUGUUAUUCUGAAUUACUGAUGGGUUCACUGAUGGAAUUAUUGAGUAUAGCCAAUAAGGAGAACCACAAUUAAGCUGGUAUCUCUGGGUUCUGGAUAUCAUCCUCAAGAAAACUAUUUACUAAUUACAUUGAAUGAGGUUAUUAAAAUGUGUAAGUUUCACACAAAAACAAAAAGACAAUUCAUUCCAAAUUGUGCAUAUGGAUAUAUAAUGUUAAUUAUGGGAAUUCCAUUUUAAGAAUUACUACAAUUCUAUGUGUUCUGUAUAAAAACAGGAAAAUAGUUGUUCCAAUAUAUAAAAGGAAAACAUUUAAAAAUGUAUUUUGUUGGGAAAAUCAGUUGCCAGAAUUCAUUCAGUCAACUAACAAGCACUCCUCUGUGGCAAGAAGCCCUGCCUCUCUGUUGUAGCAGGCAGCUACCCACCUAAAUGAUGAGGUCAAGAAAUAUACAGCUGAUAAAAAGAUAAAAAAUAUGUAAUAGUCCAGUGAUUACAUGUGUACUAUGGAUCAGUGCCAAUUACUUGUAAGCUUUUGGUAUUUAGUUUGUUACAGCAAAUGUUUUCUUUUUUAAAUUUUCUUCUGCAAAUGUUUUCUUGUCAUGAAAACUGUUUCCCAUUUGGCAGAAUUACAAAAAUAGUCAAGAAGAAAUGUUCUGAUUGAUGUAUACAGUUAGAAUGUGUAUUAAAGAUUAUUAUAAAAUGAUAACUGAAUUAUAUCCAUUUCUAAAGUAUGUUGGGACAGAAUUUUUUAAAAAUGUGAUUCUGUUUUGAAAAUUGUUUUACCACUGGAUCAGUGUGGUUCUUAAACUUGGCUUUAUCUUGGAGUCACCAGAGGAGAUUCAAAAGAUACCAUUACCUGGCUCUACCUCCAGAGAUCGGGAUUUUAAUUGGUCUGUAUCUGGAUUUUAAGAGCCCUUCUGGUGAUUCGACUGUUUAGCUAGGUUUGAGAGCCACUACCCUAGAUUAUCUGUCCUGCUCCAGUAACAUUCUUUUUCUAAAAUCAUUUAUAGUAUAUUAGAAAUAAAUCCAUGGAAAUUCCAAGUAAAAUCAGAAUUACUGGGGUUUUUCUCUGGAACUGAAAUUCCUAUGUGUGAAUAAUGCCCAAGAAUUGCUUAUUCCUUUCACCAGCCAAACAAAGCAAAACAAACAAACAAACAAAAACCAUUUAAAAACCUAGUAAGAUGUUGACUUACCAGAUAUUAAAGCAUACUAAAAGCUUCUAUACUAGAAUCAGUAUGGUAGUGGAUAGGAACAGAGAAGUCAGUAGAACAGUCAAGAUCUCAGAAAGAUCCCAGUUUAUGUGCAAAGUUGUUAGUAACAAGGAAUGUGGCUCAAUUCAGUGGAACAGGGAUGAAUUAUUUCUGAAAUUCUGCCGGAACAAACAAGUGUCCAUAAGGCAGAAAAUAAGCAUGAUCACUAUCUUAUACACACUAAGAAUAUGUAAAUUAAAGAGGAUGAGAAACAAACAACAAUCUUAAAGAAAAUCUAUGAGAUUGUAUGUAGGACCUAGGGUAGUAUGAAACUUUCUUAACAAAGAUUGGAAACUCAGAAGCUGUAAAAUACAAUAUAGACAUAAUUGACUAUAUAAAAACAUCAAUGUUUUCAUGCUAAAAAUACUAUAUGCAAACAUUGCAUAUAACUAUUAGAUCUGAAAACCAUUUGAAAGGCUGUCAAAUAUAACUUUCCAACAGCUAAAAAUAUGACCCAUACAAAUAUCAAAUAAGCAUGUGUCAAAGAUUUAGUCAAUUCAUUAAUGAGGGAACCAGUAAAAUAGUAAGCUGGUUCAAAAGAGAUUUUGAGGAUUGUGUAGAGAAGACCAAAUGUUGCUCAGGAGAAAGACUGAGUAUGAAAAUGUCCUGUUAUUUGCUGUAUCCUCAGGGCUAGCACAGGGCCUGGAAAAUAGCUGGCAUAGAUUAAACUCCUGUUGAACUAAAAUUAUAUUGAGACUCCUUUACUAAUGCUGAGAAGUAGAGAAGUGGAGAAUUUCUCACACACACACAGAAAGCCACAUGGAUGUGUGCCCAAUUAUAAUAAUACUUAUGUUGAAAGAGAAGAUAAAUGUUAUAGAUUUCAGCUUUAGCAGGCAGACUAAUCCUGGAUUGAUAAAAAGCCUUGUACGUCUUCGUAAAAUCUGGCUUUAAUUAGAUAGAAGCACCACCUGUAAGGCUGCUCAAUGUGCUCUUUUGUUUUAU